GUGGUUGUUCUUGUUCCAGGAUCCCAUCUGGAAUACCACGUUAUAUUUGUCAUUAGAUUUGUCAUGUCUACUUAGGCUCCUCUGGGUUAUAAGUUGACCUCCUCUUGAUCUCAGCUCACUGAAACCUCUGACUCCCGGGUUCAAGCUAUUCUUGUGCCUUAGCCUCCCAAGUAGCUGGGAUUACAGGCAUGUGCUACCACGCCCAGCUAAUGUUUUGUAUUUUUAGUAGAGAUGGCGUUUAGCCAUGUUGGCCGAGCUGGUCUCGAACUCCUGGACUCAAGUGAUCCGCUUGCCUCAGCCUCCCAAAGUGCUGGGAUUACAGGCAUGAGCCACUGUGCCCGGCCACAAAUAGAUAUUUUAAAUAUGACAAUAAUACAUGCUUUGGAGAAAGGUAAAGCAGGAUAAGGGAGUAGGGGGUUCUGAGGUGGAAUGAUGGGACUGUUACUUAUAUACAGCAGUUGAAGAAAGCCCCAUUGCUAAGGUGGCAUUUGAGCAGAGACAGGGAGGAAGCAAGGGAAUGAGCCAUGCGCAUACCACUAGGAAGAGUAUUUCAGGCAGAGGGAGCAAACAGUGCAAAAGCCUGAAGCAGGAGUGGCUUGGAACACUCCAGGAACAGCAGGUUGGUCCAUGAGCCUGGAGCAGGGUCAGCCAGGUAAUGAGAUGGAGUGAGUGAGGACAAACACAAAUUUGGGCAGGUGGUGUCUGGGAUGGAAUCACGGAAAGCGCAUGUGAGUGGCUGUCGUGGGAGCUGUGUACUGCUGUGGAGUUGGGCUAUAGAGGUCCUUGUGGGGACUUGGUCUUUUUCUUUGAGGAGAGAGGAGCUAUUGGAGGCUUUUGAGCAGAGGAAUAGGGUCAUCUGAUUUCAUAUUUGAAAAGGACCACUCUGGUCACUCUGAAUGUUGCAGAAGUAGAAAGACCAGUUAAAAAGUCUUUUACUCUACUAGUAUAUUUUAUCUUAAUCUAUUAAUCUUGAUCUAUUUGUAUGCAUAUUUCACAUGUAGUAAUUGUGUACAUACAGUUUUGCCAUCUGUGUAUUUUAACAUUUUUUUUCUGUUGCUCUGUAGUCCUCAGGUUUAUAACAUUCAGUGGCUGCAUAAUAGUUUGUGUAUUAGUCUCCUACUGCUGCUGUAAAAACUUACCACAAAUGGAAUGGCAUAAAAGGAUACAAAUUUAUUAUCUCACAGUUCUGGAGGUCAGAGUCCUAAAAUCAAGGUGUUGGCAGAGCUGCACUCCUUCUGGAGGCUCCAGGGAGAAUCCAUUUCCUUGCUUCUUCCAUCUUUUAGAAUCCACCCUCACUCCUUGACUCAUGGCCUCUCACUCCAUCUUUAAAGCCAGCAGCAUCUUCAAACCUCACCUCUGCUUCAGUCACCACUUCUCCUAUUCUGAACCUCCUGUCUCCCACUUCUACACACUUUUGUUAUUACUUUGGGUGCAUUUGGAUAAUCUCCCCAUUUUGAGGCACUUAAUUUAAUUACAUCUCGAAGAUUCCUUUUACCAUGUAAAGUAGUAUAUUCACAAGUUCUGGGGAUUAGGAUGUGGACAUCUUUGGGGACAUUAUUCAGCCUACCACAGCUGAUGUUUUGUAGUUUACUUAACCAUUCCCAUUGUUGAAUACUUAGAAGGCAUCCAGUUUGGGGCCAUUUUGAUAUUCCUAUACUUCCUAUAAUUAUAUACUUUGACCUUCUUUUCUUUCAGAUUGUGUCUCUUAAGAUAAAUAUCCAAGUUUAGGUUUCCUGGAACAAAGAGCAUGAACAUCUUAUGUAUUUGCUUCCAAAUACAGUUAAAUUAUUGGUAAAUAUAUAAGGAUGUCAGUUUCCCUACAACGUCACCAGGUUUGCUUUCUGUCAAUUAAAGGUGUGUUUCCAGUUUGUUACAAAAUGACAUUUUAUUGGUGUGUUUAUUUUAUUUCCUUGCUGGCUAGGUUGAACCUUUUUGGAGUGUGCAUGGCGGCAUAUGUCAUUUGUAUUUUGAGAAUAGUGUUAUGUUUAUUUUGCUUUUUAGUUGUAUCUGGAGCUAGAAGAAUGGGGACAGGAUUAGACUAUUGCUUAAGUAAGGGCAUAAGGCUAGCAUGAAUAGAUGAUGUAUGCAGAACUAUGUUGCUUUCAAUUCUCCAUCAAAGGAAGUGAUUUCCAAAAUUAAAAGGGUGUUACUAAAAGGGAUUUGGAUGACAAUGAAAGAAAAUCCAGGUAAUUUGAAUGCAUUUACCUCUCUGGGGCACACUGGAUUGUAUCUCAGGGUUAGCAGGGUUGAAGGAGUUAGCAGGCAUCAUCUUUGAGCCAUUGCUGGUGAUUGUUGAGUGAACUUGGAGAGUGGCAGAGGUUCCAGAAGACCAGAGAUAUGCAAAUGUUGUUCUAUAUAGCUUUUGACAAAGUUGAAUUCCUAAAACUUUCAAUGUGUGAAAUGCACCCUUGCAAAAUUUCUGAACUAUCAUCAUAUAAAUUAUUUAGGAGUCCAGAGAAGAGAUUGCAUUGAUCCUUAGGAACCAGCAUAAAUCUACUAAUGCGUAGUGACCAAUUGUCACAUUUUCUUUUAUAAAAGGGGCUUCUAUAUUGGAAGAUAAUGCCAAAGACAUCAAAGCAUUUGACAAAUAUCUCUCACCGGUCUCCUUACGCACAUAAUAGAGAGAUGUUGGAGGAUGACAGAAUAAUGCAAUAAAUUCAUAGCUGAUUCUAUUCAUAUGCCAUAACAUAGGUAAUGACUGAGUGUUCGUCAGCCUAGAAAGAGGUUUCUAGUGGCAGGUAUUUAGGGUUUUCUUGGCCCCAAACUGAAGCAGGAUCCUUAGAACUUGGAUAGAGAUCUGAAAAAUUCAUAUGUAUGUGGCUGAUGAUGUAAACCUAUAGAAUAAAUCUUCAUAAUAUGAACUAUGAAAAUAGGCCAACACCAACUAGGUACAUUUAACAGAAAUAAUGAGAACUUCUAAAAUUGAGGUUGUAUUUAUAAUUGAAACAACAGUUGAUUUUCUUUAUUUUUGGCCGUCUUGAAUUUCACCAAUUAAAAACAGUAACACUUGUAUAGUGAAAAUGACUUUUUAAGGUUAAUUCAUGUAUGGUAGGAGAAUGCUGGGUCCACCUACAUAUGGUUGCUAUGAGAGCAUGCUAUAAUAAAGAAUUGCUGGACUGAGAGGAAAAGAUGUGAGUACUGUUCCUGUCACCACCAUAAACUAGUUGUCAUCUUGGGCCAGCAGUUGGCAUCACCUUCCUUGGAUCUGCGUAUUCUCAUCUGAAAGCUGGAGAUGACAAGGGGUGGGGUGAAGUUAGUCACUUUGCUCCAUUCCGGCUGUCAUGUGAUAUGAGGCAGUACAACUUGAUUCUCAUGUUCCUUGGCGAGUUUGGCCAAAUUUCUAGACUUUUAAAUGGACCCUUCCACAUAUUUCUAGCUUAAACAGACCCUUUCAGGCCCUCUCUGAGAAGGGGCCCCUUUUCUUUUAAUCUGCAAGUUCCUUCAGAUCACCCUUCUUCAGGAUCAUAUUAAACUAUCCACAUUUUCAACGCUUCAAUCCAAGUUUCAAACAGUGUACUUGAGCCCACUUUGAUCUCAGGAAGGCCAACAUUUUUUUUUUCUUCUUUUUGGGCUCAGGCCCAUGCCUCAACAUUUCUGGAUGAGCCUAUACCCUCUUCUUCACCGGCCAAAAAAGUUCUCCAUGGCUUUACCAUGGGGUCCAGCCUUCAGUUUCUUCAUUCUCCGUCAGCCGACCCUGAACAAUCCUGGCCACCGUUGGCAUUUGAUCAUCGACUGUUUCUCUAGCUUCCUCCCCAGCACCACUAUUUUGAUUCUGCUGUAAUCUUUAUGACCAUUUAAUUUUGAAUUUUUAAACUUCAUAUUUUAUUUUCCUAUUUCAUAUCUUCACAUUAUCAUUUGUAAAGGAGUUUAAAAUAUUUCAUGUGCCUCGAUUUACUCUUGCAUAGUCUGAUUUUCCCCUCUUAUCAGUCCUCAAAUAUCAUCAACUCUUUGUUUUCUGCUCUUAUGGGACGCAACAUUUGUACAUCUUCAUACAAUCUAGCCUUUGGCUUCUUUUGUCUAUAUACUUAGAUUAACCUCUCAGAGUUGGAGAUCUUUGACUGAGGGAUAUAGUAGUAUAGUUCUUGAUCCAUUUUGGGUACCUUUAUUUUGACUGACAAAGACAAGAGGCCACGUUAGCACAUUAUAUUCUUUCCUUAAAACUUUAAAAUAUUUAAGAAGGCAGCAUUUAUAUUUAAACAUAAAUUUCAGCCUCCUUCUUGGGGCUUCCCUUAAUACCAAAGUAAUUUUGGUUGGAGGAAUGUUUUGCAGGCUGUGAUAUCUCAGAUUGCAACACUUCUCAGCCUGCUGUUUCCUGUGCUUCUCCUCCAGCUCCUUCCACUGAGAAUUCUCCCCAGGCAGCAUUUUCACGCUUUCAGUGCUCAUUUCAGGCACUCUCUGCUCUGCUGUGCCUAUGCAUGCUUGAGGCUUUGCCCUAAACUCAUGUGACCUGCAUAGCUAAUUUCAGGUUCUCAGUCUAGGCUUACUACUGCUGAACCCAAGAGACUGAUGUAUUGCCCAGACUCCUGCACGCUGUCUGCCAGCCACAGGUACAUUCUGGGGUCAUGUAUUAUGCUCCUGGUUAGCACAUUGGGCAGGGAACAAGCUACCCAUUGUGGCUGUGACCAGGUAUAGAGUCUCUGCUUAUCUGAAAAACAGUUCUUUGACCUCACUACCUGUGGCCAUUCCUUCCUGCUACUGUGUCCUUGAUCAGCCAGCUCCCCACCCUUUGCCUAGAAAGCAUUCCCAAUCCCUACCAGUAAGAUAAAGGGAGCAAAACAGAAAGCCAGUUCUGUGUGGCCCAAGGCUCUGCUAUAUAUGUGUUUGCAUCCAGUGUCUGAAUUUUCUCCCUGAAGAAAUGGAAGAUCUUGGGACGGAUCUUUUGAUGAGGAAGCCAAGGCCCAGCAGAGCUGAGAUGUGACUGCAGAGCCGUCCAACCCCAGUCCUGUGACCUUUCUCUGGUGCCUGAUACCUCUCAGCAUUUGAGGGCCUUUUCUCUUCCUGCUUCAUCUCUAAAGGUCCUUCUAGGAGAGAGGUGAAAGAAACCUGGCAAAGAAAACGGUCUCGACAAUGAGUAGGCCACCCAUCACUACUAACUACAGAUGACUUGCCAUUUCAUUUACAAAGAUGUCUUCUGCUGCUGAAAAUGGAGAGGCAGCACCUGGAAAACAAAAUGAAGAAAAAACCUAUAAAAAGACUGCAUCAUCUGCUAUUAAAGGUGCUAUUCAGCUGGGAAUAGGAUACACAGUGGGUAAUCUCACUUCCAAGCCAGAACGAGAUGUUCUUAUGCAAGACUUUUAUGUGGUGGAAAGUGUGUUCCUACCCAGCGAAGGGAGCAAUCUGACCCCAGCACAUCACUACCCAGACUUUAGAUUUAAGACAUACGCUCCAUUAGCAUUCCGAUAUUUCAGAGAACUUUUUGGUAUCAAGCCUGAUGAUUACUUGUAUUCCAUCUGCAGUGAACCUCUAAUAGAACUGUCUAACCCUGGAGCCAGUGGAUCCUUGUUUUUUGUGACCAGUGAUGAUGAAUUUAUCAUCAAAACAGUUCAGCACAAAGAAGCUGAGUUUCUUCAGAAGCUACUGCCAGGCUAUUACAUGAAUUUAAACCAGAAUCCAAGGACUCUUUUGCCAAAAUUUUACGGACUGUAUUGUAUGCAAUCAGGAGGCAUUAAUAUCAGGAUUGUGGUGAUGAACAACGUUUUGCCACGCUCCAUGAGAAUGCACUUUACAUAUGACUUGAAAGGCUCAACGUAUAAGCGAAGAGCAUCCCGUAAAGAGAGAGAGAAAUCCAACCCCACAUUUAAGGACUUAGAUUUCCUGCAAGACAUGCACGAAGGGUUGUAUUUUGAUACGGAAACAUACAACGCGCUUAUGAAAACACUUCAGAGAGACUGCCGGGUGCUAGAAAGCUUCAAGAUCAUGGAUUAUAGCCUUCUGUUGGGAAUUCAUUUCCUGGACCAUUCCCUCAAAGAGAAAGAGGAGGAGACCCCACAAAAUGUGCCUGAUGCUAAGCGGACUGGGAUGCAGAAGGUUCUCUACUCAACAGCCAUGGAAUCUAUCCAGGGUCCAGGGAAAUCUGGAGAUGGGAUAAUCACAGAGAACCCAGACACAAUGGGAGGCAUUCCAGCUAAAAGCCAUAGGGGAGAAAAACUACUUUUAUUUAUGGGCAUUAUUGACAUUCUGCAAUCAUAUAGGUUAAUGAAGAAGUUAGAACAUUCCUGGAAAGCUCUUGUUUAUGAUGGGGACACUGUUUCUGUUCAUAGACCAAGCUUUUAUGCAGACAGAUUUCUUAAGUUCAUGAAUUCCAGAGUUUUCAAGAAAAUUCAAGCUUUGAAGGCUUCACCGUCUAAGAAACGGUGCAAUUCAAUCGCCGCCCUAAAGGCCACUUCACAGGAGAUUGUGUCCUCAAUUAGCCAGGAAUGGAAGGAUGAGAAGCGGGAUUUGCUGACUGAAGGACAAAGUUUUAGCAGCCUUGAUGAAGAAGCCCUGGGAUCCCGACACAGGCCAGACCUGGUCCCUAGCACUCCAUCACUGUUUGAAGCUGCUUCCUUGGCAACCACAAUUUCAUCUUCUUCCUUAUACGUCAAUGAGCACUAUCCACACGACAGGCCUACACUCUAUUCAAACAGCAAAGGGUUACCUUCCAGUUCAACAUUUACCUUGGAAGAGGGGACCAUCUACUUGACCGCUGAGCCCAACACUCUGGAAGUGCAGGAUGACAAUGCUUCUGUGCUUGACGUCUAUUUAUAAGUGAAAAUGGUGAUCACCUAAGCACAUGGAUGAGACGUGAGCACAGUUAUGGCAGAGAAGUUUCUCCGCACCAGAAUUAUCCACAGCAACUUGGCUGAGCCCCACUACACACAGAGAAAUCAUCAACCUGACUUAAGAGUUUUCAAGAUGUCAACUUCAGGCUGAUCAGCAGAUGGGAUGUGAAAAAUACUACCCUAUUCUAUCAUUUGCUGUUGCUUGCUGAACUGUGAAGAACUGCAUGAACUAUAUUUAAGCUGCUUUCUGUACCAUUGCCAAUCACCUUUUUGGAGUUGGAAGUGCUAUUUUCCUAUGGACUUUUGCAUUAUUUCAUUGUGCAUGCAUCCAGUGAUUAUACAUAAGCAACAUAUGUAAUCUGCUUAUAUAUUUUUAAAAAUCCAUCCACACACAUGGUAAAUUAAGUAUAAAUUCUUUUGCAAAAUUAUAGUUCAUGUCAUUGAAAGUUUAAAUUGGUUUCAUUUAAAGAUCAAUAUACUAGGUCUGCCUUCACUUUAUAGAAAACUAGCUUCUAUAAAGAUUUUUUCACUGUUUACUAGUGAAAUGAGAAAAGCAAAGCUAUUUAUAAAAGGCCUUAUGUCGUGUACAUACAUUGUCUUUGAAAUAUUUGUGAUCUAGUUUAUUGCUUGUAAAAGAGAAAUUAUAUAAUUUAUUUAGUAAAUACUACUGUAAACUAUAGUUUUGUGAGAGAAAUAAAAUAUUUUGUUCUCAA